GACGUCCACACCUCAGAAGCAUCUUCUUGAAACCCAUCUCAAUUCUCUCCUCUUGACAACAUGUGUUGCAACUACUACGGCAACUCCUGUGGCUAUGGCUCCAGCUAUGGCUGUGGCUAUGGCUCUGGUUAUGGCUGUGGCUAUGGCUCCAGCUAUGGCUGUGGCUAUGGCUCUGGUUAUGGCUGUGGCUAUGGCUCCAGCUAUGGCUGUGGCUAUGGCUCUGGCUACAGCUGUGGCUAUGGCUCUGGCUCUGGCUGUGGCUAUGGAACUGGCUACGGCUGUGGGUAUGGCUGUGGUUAUGGAACUGGCUAUGGCUGUGGAUGUGGCUCUGGCUCUGGCUACUGUGGCUACCGGCCAUUUUGCUUUAGAAGAUGCUAUUCUUCCUGCUAAAACAUCACUGUCAGAGGACAAUUUGCUUCUAAAAUGACACGGCUAAAGAUAAUACUGAUUCAAGGAUUCAUACUCCAAGAUUUCUAUAUCCAAGAAUUACAUGCUUGACAGAGUCUUGGACCUCUAGCCUCACAUUUCUUUGAAUGAAAUCAUGGCCAUAGGAUCCACGGUGUCAUCUGACUGUUUUCCAAAUGUUAUCUUUUGCUCCCUUAAUCUCUGACUCUCUGUUAUGACUGUGUUAAUGAUCAUAACAUCUACAAUUGGGGAAGUCAAUCAUUUGUAAUAAAAAUGGUUCUUUAUUCC